CCCCCUCGGGCGGGACCGCGGACGCCUGGAGGCAGGCACUGAGGACGGGGAGAACUUCGGGUGAAAUGCAUCCCUCCUGUGACUGGAUUGGAGACACAAGAACAGAAACAUCCUGAUCUCUCUACUCUACUGUGCAGGCUUAUGUACUCAUAAAAUGGCAGUUAUGGACCUAUCCUCCCCAUGGGCUUUAACUAAACAGGACUCUGCCUGUUUCCAUCUGAGAAAUGCUGAAGAGGAAAGGAUGAUUGCUGUAUUUCUGACAACCUGGUUACAGGAACCAAUGACUUUCAAAGAUGUAGCUGUGGAGUUCACUCAGGAGGAGUGGAUGAUGCUGGAUUCUGCUCAAAGAAGUCUGUACAGAGAUGUGAUGUUGGAAAACUAUAGAAAUCUCACCUCCGUGGAAUAUCAGUUGUACAGGCUUACUGUGAUCUCCCCAUUGGAUCAAGAAGAGAUAAGGAAUAUGAAAAAGAGAAUUCCCCAAGCCAUCUGUCCAGACCAGAAGAUUCAACCUAAAACCAAAGAAUCAACUGUGCAGAAAAUUUUGUGGGAGGAACCAUCCAAUGCAGUGAAAAUGAUAAAACUCACAAUGCAUAAUUGGUCCUCCACAUUAAGAGAAGACUGGGAAUGCCAUAAGAUCAGAAAACAGCAUAAGAUUCCAGGGGGACAUUGGAGGCAAAUGAUAUAUGCCCCAAAGAAAACAGUACCUCAGGAGCUAUUCCGUGACUAUCAUGAAUUAGAGGAAAACUCUAAACUUGGAUCAAAACUUAUUUUUUCACAGAGCAUUUUCACCAGUAAACAUUGCCAAAAAUGUUACUCAGAGAUUGGAUGUUUGAAACACAAUUCAAUCAUAAACAAUUAUGUGAAAAACUCUAUAAGUGAGAAGCUCUAUGAAAGUCAUGAAUGUGAUACAACUCUAUGGCAUUUUCAGAGAAAUCAAACAGUACAAAAAGAGUACACAUAUUCUAAACAUGGAAUGCACUUCACACAUAAUAUGUUUCCUGUACCUAACAAUUUGCAUAUGGCACAGAAUGCCUGUGAAUGUAAUAAAGAUGAAACGCUGUGUCAUCAAUCAUCCCUUAAGAAACAAGGACAAACUCAUACUGAAAAGAAACAUGAAUGCAAUCAAUGUGGAAAAGCCUUCAAAAGGAUUUCUAAUCUUACUUUAUACAAGAAAAGUCACAUGGGUGAGAAACAAUAUGAAUGUAAAGAAUGUGGUAAAGUGUUCAAUGAUUCCUCAACCUUAAGGAGACAUGUAAGAACUCACACUGGAGAGAAACCCUAUGAAUGUAAUCAAUGUGGAAAAGCUUUCAGUCAAAAAACAUCCCUUAAGGCUCACAUGAGAACUCACACUGGAGAGAAACCUUAUGAAUGUAAUCAGUGUGGAAAAUCCUUUGGCACAAGCUCUUACCUUAUAGUGCACAAGAGAAUACACACUGGAGAAAAACUCUAUGAAUGCAGUGAGUGUGGAAAAGCCUUCAACACGAGCUCUCACCUUAAAGUUCAUAAGAAAAUUCAUACCGGAGAGAAUGUUUAUGAAUGCAGUGACUGUGGGAAAGUUUUCAGUGGGGUCUCAUCCCUUAGAAUGCAUAUAAGAACUCACACUGGAGAGAAACCCUAUGAAUGUAAGGAAUGUAGGAAAGCCUUCAGUGUUUCCUCUUCCCUUAGGAGGCAUGUGAGAAUUCACACUGGAGAGAAACCCUAUGAAUGUAUUCAAUGUGGAAAAGCCUUCAGUCAGAGCUCUUCACUUAUUAUACACAAGAGAAUUCAUACUGAGAGAGAAACCCUGUAAGUGUUAUGAAUGUGGAAUUGCUGUUUUCAUUGUCUUAAGGUGGAUUCCAAGCUCCUUGUCUCAGUCUUUGUUCUCUAAAAGAACGAUUUAAGGUUACAAAUGGCUCUUUUUUUAAUAUAACAUUUUCUGUAAAUACUAAUUAUGACUUUUUUUGAUCCAUGGCUGUUUAGAAUUAGGUAUUUUUAAUAUGUGAGGUAGGUAUAUUUUCAGUUAUCUUUUUAUUGUUGGUUUCUAGGUUAAUUCCAUUGUGUUCAGAGAAUCUGGACUAUAUUUUACUGCUUUGUUGGUGUUUUUAUAAAAGUUGUUUUCUGGCCCAGUGAGACUGGUAUUGCUAGCAGCCAACCAAACAUUUGAGCUCAUCUUUCCUUACUAAUGAAUUCCAUCUUAGCCAAGAACAAUAAGGUCUCUGGUUAUAGAACGCUUCUUUGACUUCUUGUAGCUAAGGGUAGCCAUAUCAUUCAUUCUUGCUGAUUCAAAAAUAGACAUAUCACUGGGAUCAGAACUAUCUAUCUUGUCCUCUACUUUUUGCACUUCAUCUUUGUCCCUAUGAAUUGGCCAUUCCUGAAGCUGCUGAAAGAGCUAUCUUGUGAUCAUGAAAAUGACAGCUGUAGCCAAGGGAUGAAGUAGAAGAAAGAGAUCCCUGUUCCUCAAAGAAAUCUUUAAAUAGUUGUACCAGCCCUGCACUACUUGUAUCUGGAUAUGUUCCUACAUGAGAAAAAUAAGGUUUUUUGUUUGUUUUUUGAGAUGGAGUCUCGGUAUGUUGCCCAGGCUGGAGUGCAGUGGCACAAUCUCAGCUCACUGCAACCUCCACCUCCCAGGUUCAGGUGAUUCUCCUGCCUCAGCCUCCUGAGUAGCUGGGAUUACAGGCACCACCGCCAUGCCUGGCUAAUUUUAGUAUUUUUAAUAGAGACGGGGUUUCACCAUGUUGGCCAGGUUGGUCUCAAACUCCUGACCUCAGGUGAUCCACCCACCUAGGCGUCCCAAAGUGUUGGCAUUACAGGCGUGAGCCACUGUGCCCGGCCAAGAAAAAUAUGUUAAUUGAUUUUUUCUUUUUUUUUUUCAAUUUUUCAGACAGAGUCUCUGUCUCUCAGGCUAGAAUGCAGUGGUGUGGUCAUGGCUCAUUGCAACCUCGACCUCCUGGGCUCAGGUGAUCCACCACAGUCUCCUCAGUAGUUGGGAUCACAAAUGCAUGCCACCAUGCCUGGCUAAUUUUAAAAAUAUAUAUUUUGUAGAGACAGGCUCUUCCUACAUUGCUCAGACUGGUCUGAAACUCCUGGGCUCAAGCAGUCCUCCUGCCUUUGCCUCCCAAAGUGCUAGGAUUCCAGGCAUGAGUUACCAUGCCUGGCUCUUACUGAUUUUUUUUAAAGCACUACAUAAAUACAGUCAACGCAGUCACCAUAUUGUAGAAAAACAGAAGUAUAUACAGUUAAAUGUUUUAUGUUGGAUGUACACAUUUGAAGAGGAACAUAGAAAAAAAGUAUGGAAAAGGAAUGUUGACCGAGCUUUUAUGCUUAAGCAGCAGAUGAAGAUAGAACCAAGAUCACUGAAAGCAAGUGUUUAGAACAGCAAAAAGAGUAUCCCAACAUUUCAGCAUUGGAACUACAGAAAGUUUUCAGACAGAGGGGAAGUUACCAAUUUUAAAUGCUAAGUAAAGCAUGAGAUUUUGCUGCUUGAUCUUGCAGAUACUGACCAGAUUAGUUCUAACAAAAUAUGGAAGGAGUGGCAUACGGUGGAAGAAAGAAGGCAGUAGCUGCUGUUGUAGUUAUUCAUGUUAGCCUCAGAGGAUGGUGAGACAUCCAGAUGAAGAGGUUGGUACGCAAUUCUAGAAUUGAGGAGGUGUCUAGAUAGAGAUAUAAAUUGUAGUGACAUCAGUAAAGAGACAAUAACAGGCUUUGGAAGGUGAGUAAGAAUGAAAAGGGAAGGUCUGCCACCUACCCUGAAGACAUACAUUUAAAGGAACUAUAGUAGAGAGAUAAGAGGAAAACAAGAAGAGUGGAGUUUCACUGAACCAAGACAAACAAGUUUCAAAAAGGAAGGUGAAGUUGGCCAGGUGUGGUGGUUCACGCCUGUAAUCCUGGCACUUUGAGAGGCUGAGGCAGGCGGAUCACAAGGUCAGAUCGAGACCAUCCUGGCCAACAUGGUGAAACCCUGGUUCUACUAAAAUACAAAAAUUAGCCGGGUGUGGUGGCACAUGCCUGUAGUCCCAGCUACUCAGGAGCUGAGGCAGAAGAAUCACUUGAACCUGGGAGGCAGAGGUUGCAGUGAGAUGAGAUCUCACCACUGCACUCCAGCCUGGUGACAGAGCAGGACUUCAUCUCAAAAAAAAAAAAAAAAAAAGGAAGGUGAAGGUAAAUGUUUUUAGUGUUACUUAGGGAUCCAAUUAGAUGAAGUCUAAAAAGGUAAACAUAUACAGCCAAGUGAAGAUCAUUUGUGAUUGUAGUUGGAAAUAACAUAGUGGUACAUAAUGAAGAUGGUUGCUAGAUUGGGCUGACUUUAGGAAUCAAUAAAGGGCAAAGAAGUAAAGACUGGAUGUAGACAAGUUUGAAUAAUAGGAGAAAGGGUAGUAGCUGGAGAGAUUUGGAGUAAAGAGAUAAUAUGUUUAAAAUAUGAAAAACUAGAACAUGUUUGAAUUCUAAUGUGAUGAAUGUAGUAUGGUGAGGUUUAAUAUGCAGCAUAAUAAAGUUUAAUAUAAGCUUCUGAGAAUGGGGUGUAGAUGUUUAGAGCACAAACAAAAGUAUUGGUGUUUGCCAUGAGGCGGAGGGAUACUCCCACCAUUCUUUCAGGAGUAGAAAAAUGGGUGGGUUGGUUUAAAUUACUUGUUUAUUUAUUUACACCUAACUGUACUAAGCAGUGAUCAGAAUAUGUGAACUAUAUAAUGUUUUGUGUUUCCUAAGAACUGUGUGGCAGCCACUGCUAAUUACUAACCAAAUAUAUAUAUUUUUUAUUCUUUAUGAAUAGAUCUUCAGUUUUGCUAACAGUAGUAUUGUAUUUAGCUACAAAACUACUUAUCCCAACCUCUUUGUAGCCUUGAUGCCAUUUCUACUGUUCCUGGCCAGUAAAAUAUAGAUAUAUGAUUAUAGGUUUCAUGGUAAGAUUAUCUGCUAAGAGGAAGGUGGAUGAAAUUCUGCAAGGAGGUUUUAGUGAAGAAGAUCUCUAUGUAUUUGAAAGUCCUUCCAAGUUAUCAAUAGAGCCAUCAGUGGAGAAGACAGCAAAGCAAGUAGCAAAGUCUAUGUGAUUGAGGAGAGGUCAUUUAAAUAAAAGAUAGCAAGGAAGAGAGGGAGAAAGUGGUAUAACUAGAUGGUAUGAACUUCAAAGGAAGGAGUGGUUUUCUCCAGGCUGCAAUGGUUAGAAGCAGUGUUAGGGAGUAAGGAAGAUACUGAUCCCACUUCCAACCUGUGGAUAUGUGGAAUACAUGAGAAUAAGCCCCCUUGUGAUGUGAUUGUUGUCAGGUAGGUGUUUUUUCCUUCCCAGGGAACAGCCAAGUUUAAAUUAAUGAAAGGAAAUGUUCAGGGAAAUAGUUGAGGAUAUUAAGGGAGUUUAUUAAGGGAAUCUCAGAGGGCACCAUGAAAGAGUCUCCAGAAGGGCAGGGGUUUAGGGUUUCUGGCUUUGGCCUGAGGAAUACAGAAGAUUGUAAUGACAUUAUUGAUAGAGGAAAAAAGACCAGAUCAGGGGCUAUGACCAGUGAAAACAAAAUUUAGAGGGAGUAUAGGUUAAAUCCCAGCAGUCUGUAAGAAGAUGAUGGGUAUUUAGGUCUACUGGGAUUCAUUUGUAGCUUGGAAAGGAGAGCCUGCAGUCAUGCUGUGAAACCAAGUGGUUUCAGGUGUUAGCAGCCCUGGUGGGUAUAGCACUAGCCAUCAGUAGUUAGAAAAUGGUCCCAACUGGCCGGGUGCAGUGGCUCACGCUUCUAAUCCCAGCACUUUGGGAGGCCGAGGCAGGCGGAUCACGAGGUCAGGAGAUUGAGACCAUCCUGGCUAACAUGAUGAAACCUCGUCUCUACUAAAAAUACAAAAAAUUAGCCAAGUGUGGUGGUGGGCGCCUGUAGUACCAGCUACUCGGGAGGCUGAGGCAGGAGAAUGCUGUGAACCCGGGAGGCAGAGGUUGUGGUAAGCCGAGAUCGCACCACUGCAUUCCGGCCUAGGUGACAGAGCAAGACUCCGUCUCAAGAAAAUCGUCCCAACUGCAUGUGGUCCUUGGGUGAGAUCAUCUUAAGGAGUACUCAGCAAGGGAUUGUACUUUGCUUGGUUAGGACUGGAAUUUACACUCUAAUUUUGGCCCAGUGAUCUUGGAACAGAUUGAGCAUCUCAAAUCUGAAAAUCUGAAAUUCAGAAUGCUCCAAAACCUGAAACCUUGUGCGCCGAUGUGACUUUCAAAAGAAAUGCUCAUUGGAGCAUUUAAAAUUUUGGAUUUUCAGAUUUGUGAUGCUCAACUAGUAGGUAUAAUGCAAAUAUUCCAAAAUCCAAAACAGUUCUGGUCCCAAGUGUUUUGAAUAAGGAAUACUCAUCCUGUACACCAGGAGGUAGACUCAGGCACAGUCUCGCCCAGCAUCUCACCUGGAUUUUAUUGCAAUAGCCUCCUAACUGGUUUCUCUGACUUGAAUCAUACUUUCCUUUAGUAUGUUUUCUAUGCAGCUGCCAUGGUAUCCUAUUAAAAAACAAAACAAAACAAAACAAAAACUUUGUGGUUUUUAAUAAUAAAACUAAUACAUGCAUAGGAGAAAACAAUGUAAAUAACUUCUGCCCUACACAGAAGGAAACCCUGGAUUCUACUGCCUUAAAAAAUUAAUAUCGUAGGUGAAUGUGCAUUCUGUCAGACUUUAUGUACAUACAAACAUUUUAUAAAAAUUGAGUUAUACCUUUUAUCCCACAUCUUUUUUUUUUUUUUUUUUUUUUUUUUGAGAAGGAGUUUUGCUUUUUCCCAGGCUGGAGUGCAGUGGCACGUUCUCGGCUCACAGCAACCUCUGCCUCCUGGGUUCAAGCAAUUCUCCUGCCUCAGCCUCCCAAGUAGCUGGGAUUACAGGCAUGUGCCACCACUCCUGGCUAAUUUUGUAUUUUUAGUAGAGACAGGGUUUCUCCAUGUUGGUCAGGCUGGUCUCAAACUCCUAACCUCAGGUGAUCCGCCUGCCUCAGCCUCCCAAAUUGUUGGGAUUGUGAGGCCAUCGCCCCCAGCCUAUCCAACAUCUUUUUAAACAUCUUUCCAUGUCAGUGCAUGUAGUUCUAUUUCAUUUGUAAUAGCUGCUUAGUAUUUGAUUAUAUGCUUGUACCAUAAUGUAUUUGAUCCAUUUGCCUCCAGAGUUUUUAUAACAAUACUGCAAUCAAUAAUAUUGUUUAUAUAUUGUGCUUUCCUAUCAACUGUUCUCUACACUUCCCAGGGUGAUCCAUCUAAAGUACUAACCUGAUCACAUAACAUUUCACGUUUAAUCUUCUUCUGGCCUUUUUCUCCAGUUAAGAUAAAAUCUUUUUACAAGACCUUGCUCAAACUCUUGCCUUUUCAGGCCUUAUCUCUGGUUAUUCCCUUUAUCUUCACUGUCUCCCUAAUUUAACCUGUCCUAUUUAUCCUUUAGGUAUUGUGUCCUUCAUCUGCUUUAACAAUACUUGUCACACUUUCACACUGUAUUGCCUGUUUGUGUAUUGUGCCCUCUACACUGUAAGUUUUGGUAAGGUGGGAACUUUGUCUAAAUUUUUCAUUGUUUUAUUACUUGGCCCAGUGUAGGUGUUCAGUUAAAUAUUUACGGUUCUUCAGCAAAUUUUGUGCCUUUUCUUUUACUUACCAUUCUAGUGGAAGUUUAACUUAAAAGCUAUUUAAGUGAUUGUAAGGUAAAAGUUGCAAGGAGGUGGGUGCAAUGGCCUGUGCCUGUAGUCCUAUCUGCUCUGGAGGCUGACGUGGGAGGAUUGCUUGAGCCCAGGAGUUUGAGACCAGCCUGAGUAACAUGAGACUCCAUUAUAGUAAAAAUGCAUGGAAUUAAUUUUUCUUCUAGGUAUAGGAAAAUGUUGCACCAUAACAGGUGUGCAGAAACUAAGACUGUUAGGACAACAGCAGUUUAAUGUUAUUUAUAUUAUGUCCCUCUCCUAGUCCUUCUCCUCUCUUCCCUCAUCCCACUCACCACCACCCCAUUCACUACACAGACUUAUUUUUUGUAGAGCAAGUGUUCAUAUUCUGUUCCAUUAUGUAUUAUAAUAUGAAAAGGGAUGAGUUGACCAAGUAUUGGUGGGUGUGUCGUAUACUUGCUUUAGACUACCAAUGGAAGCGUAAAUUAGUACAAACUUACUGGGUGGGUGUGGUGGCUCACAUCUGUAAUCCCAGCACUUUGAGAGGCUGAGGUGAGUAGAUUGCUUGAGCCCAGGAGUUUGAAACCAGCCUAGGCAACAUGGCAAAACCCCAUCUCUACCAAAAAAAAAAAAUUACCCAUGGUGUCAUGAAUCUGUGGUCCCAGCCACUAGGGAUGCUGGGGUAGGAGGAUCACUUGAGCUGCAGUGGGGUUGAGUCUGCAGUGAGCUGUGUGCACCACUGCACUCCAGCCUGGGUGACAGAGUAAGACCCUGUCUAAAAACAAAAACAAACCAAAAAAAACUUGGGACAGUAAAGCAAUAAAUGUCCAAAGCUGGAAUAUUUAUAACCUUUAAAUAUUUAAAACCCAGCAAUUUUAAACUGAGAUUUUAUAAAAGGAUUUUUCAUGUAUAAGUAACAAUAUUCACCUGUUUCAUGCCCUAGUGAAAAACUGGAAAAUUCCUAAAUUCCCAGUAACAGUCAAUAAAAUGGAAUAUAAUGCAGUCAUUAAAAUGUAUUUGUGUGGAUUGACAUGUGGAGAUAUAUUUGAUACAUUAUGAAUUUUAAACAGUCACAAAAUAUGGUAUGACUUUUUAAUGCAUGUUAUAAAUAUGUGUGUGUGCAUUGAAAAUAUGGAAAGACAUAACACCAAAGUUUUAUCAAUGGUUAUGUCAUAAUUUUUUUCUUUUGUCUUUUUUUAAGAUGUCUAGUUUAGUGAACAGAGCUGUGGUCUAUUUCUUAAAAAUAAUUCUAUCAUUAACUUUUUAAUAAAUACUUUUUAAAGCAUGAUUUUAAUAUCUUCAAAGUUGUAAAGUAAAUAAUUUGCUUAGGCUGUUGUUGGACACAUAGAUUCUUUUCAUUUUUUUAAAUACCAGAUUAAAAAAAUUGAAAAAUAUAUUUUUUUAUAUUUUAUAAAUAUAUUUUUAAUAAAUAAAUAUAAAUAUAUAUAUAUAUAUUUUUUGAGACAGAGUCUUGCUCUGUCGCCCAGGCUGUAGUGCAGUGGCACGAUCUCUGCUCACCGCAAGCUCCACCUCCUGGGUUCAUGCCAUUCUCCUGCCUCAGCCUCCCGAGUAGCUGGGACUACAGGCGCACGCCACCAUGCCCAGCUAAUUUUUUGUAUUUUUAGUAGAGACAGGGUUUCACCGUAUUAGCCAGGAUGGUCUCGAUCUCCUGACCUCGUGAUCUGCCCGUCUCGGCCUCCCAAAGUGCUGGGGAAAAUAUAUUUUUUAACUUACCAUUUCUAUCUCCUACUUUUUAAAGGCAAACUUUUUGAAAGUGUUGAUAAAGGGUGUGGAUACUUUUUAGACUUCCUCUUACUCUAGGCAGAAUUCAAAAUAUGAAGGAUACAAAUAAGUUUCUCUGAUAAGAACAGGGAAUUGUGUUAGAAAAAGCAGUCAGGGCUAGGCGCAGUGGCGCACGCCUGUAAUCCCAGUGUUUUCGGGAGGCAGAGGUGGGUGGAUUGCCUGAGCUCAAGAGUUCAAGACCAGCCUGGGCAACAUGGUGAAACCCCAUGUCUACUAAAAAUACAAAAACUAGCUGGGCGUGGUGGCACACACCUGUAGUCCCAGCUACUGGGAGGCUGAGGCAGGAGAAUCACUUGAACCCAGGAGGCGGAGGUUGCAGUGAGCCAAGAUAGUGCCACUGCACUCCAGCCUGGGUGACAGAGCAAGACUGUGUCUCAAAAAAAAAAAAGAAGGUCUCCAUGAGAAAAUAACAUUUAACUUGAAAUACGAAGUUAAAGAAGGAGUAGGGAGCUCCUUCUUCUGGCUCCAUGGGCAGAGGGUGGAGGGACAGAGGAAGAGCUUUCUAAAUAGAACAGCAAGAGCAAAAAGACUCAUCAGGAUUUGACAUAUUUGUGGAACAGAAAGUAAGUCCAGUAAAUGGAAAACUGUUAGGCAAAGGGGUAAGGAGAAGAGUAUGUGAAACCAGAUUGAAAGGAGGCAGGGGCCAGAUAAAGACCUUGCUAGCUAUGACAUGAGUUUAUACUUUAUUUGAAGAGUUAUGAGGAACUAUUUAAGUUUUUCAGAGAUUGAAAUUAUUUGUUUUAAAAAGAUCACAUUUUUGUAUAAAAAAAUCUUGAGAGACUAGGAAGCUAUUUGCAAUAGUUCAUGUAUGAAAUUUGAAUGCCAAAAACUAAUUUCCUUAGCAUUCACUUUUUUAUUUAUUUUUCUUUAUUUUUUAAUUUUCUGUAAGUUACUGGGUUUCCUUUUUAAUUUUUCCAUAAGUUGCAUUCACUUUUUAAAAGACAAUGAGAUUUGUUUUAGCAUAAACAGGAAAUUCAUGGCUAAUACAUGUCAUGACUUAAAUUCACCUCUAACUUAAGAAAUGCAUGUCAAAUACAUAAAAUUAUAUUUUCUACCUAUGAGCACAGUUUCAUGGGAGUUUUGAUUUUUCUAAAAUAUUUUUUGAUGCAAUAUCCAUUUUUUUCCAUGCAAUUUUGUCCUUUGUGAUAUUGAGGGUGUUCAUGAUGCAGAAUUUAUUUUAAAAAAUUAUUUCUGUAAUAUUUAUUUCUCCCUUUUUUUGAGACAGUGUCUCACUCUUGCCCAGACUGGAGUGUAGUGGCACAAUCUCAGCUCACUGCCACCUCAACCUUCUGGGCUCAUGUGAUCCUCCUACCUCAGCCUCCUCAGUUGUGGGGACCACAGGCAUGUGCUAUUACACCUGGAUAAUUUUUUUAUUUGUAUUUUUUGUAGAAAUGGGGUCUCACUGCAUUGCCCAGGCUGGUAUCAAACUCCUGGGCUCAAGCAAUCUUUCUGCCUUGGCCUCCCAAAGUGCUGGGUUACAUAAUUUAUUUUUUUUUGUUUUGUUUCCUUAAAAGAAUUGUUAACAUACCAGAUAAUUUUUUACACUUUUUGCCACUUUUUCUAUGUCCUGCCUUUUAAAGGCAGACUUUUUGAAUGAGUUGCUAAGGACUCAGACUCUUUCUUCCAAAUCAAUCAUACCCAAUAGGCAGGUUUUGCUACCUCUCUUUGCUCUGAAAUUUCUUGGAUCUCUUCAGAGGGAUUUAACAAAUUUCCUGUCCUUUUUCUCUUUUCUUUUUCUUUUGUUGGUUUUGUUUUGUUUUGUUGAGAUGGAAUCUUGCUUUGUCGCCCAGGCUGGAAUACAGUAGCGUGAUCUCGGCUCACUGCAACCUCCACCUCCUGGGUUCAAGUGAUUCUCCAUGCCUCAGCCUCCAUGAGUAGCUUGGAUUACAGGCAUGCACCGCCACACCCAACUAAUUUUUUGUAUUUUUAGUAGCAAUGGGGUUUCACCAUGUUGGCCAGGCUGAUUUUAAACUCUUGACCUCAAGUGAUCUGCCUGCCUCAGCCUCCCAUGCUGGGAUCAUGCUGGGAUUACAGGCACAAGUCACUUAGCCCCCUGCCUUACAUACAUUGAUGUAUGAUAGAAAAUUCUUUUGGGCACAUCACAGCAACAAAAGUUAACCCAGCUUUACCUAUUUGUGAGUAUCUUAAGUCUCCCAAAGCAUUUGAUUGUUGCUUUCCAAGAAAAUACAGAAUUGUGGUCAUUCUCCCAUGACUAUUCUUUACUAAUAUUGAUUGCAUCUGUUGUUCUGUCGCCUUUCUGCAUUCAUAGUAACUUCUUUUUCCAAUGCUGAAGAUUAGUUUUAAUAACCUUUUGGGAGACUUCUUUUAAAAAACUUUUUUUUCCUGAAGAAUAAUACAUAAAGGCAUGCAGCUUUAUGAAUUUCCCCAAAUAGAACACACUUAACCAGUCCCCAGAUCAUGAGAGCCAAAUUAAUACUUUUACUACUUUUGCAAUAUUCCUAGACUCAUCUUUUAAACGUCUCCCUCCUUUCUUGUGCUAUUGUCGUGCUAUUUACUUCGGUGUAUUUUAUAAUCCACCAGAUAUUGUUAUGAAAGUAAAUAUUUAUAUCAGAGUUGACAAACUUUGUCUGAAGGUCCUGAGAGUAAAUAAAUAUUCUAGGUUUUCUUUUUUUUUGAGACGGAGUCUCGCUCUGUCACCCAGGCUGGAGUACAGUGGCGCAAUCUCAGCUCACUGCAAGCUCCGCCUCCCAGGUUCACGCCAUUCUUCUGCUUCAGCCUCUCAAGCAGCUGGGACUACAGGCGUCUGCCACCACGCCCGGCCAAUAUUCUAGGUUUUGCAGGCCAUAUAUGGUAACUGUUGCAUAUUCUUAUUUUUCUAAGCAGCUUUUUAAAGAUGUUAAAAUCAUUCUUAGCUCAAAGGCCUUGAUUUGGUCCAUAGACCAUAAUUUCCCAACACCUGACUUGUAUUUAUCAACAUAUUUACCCCUCCAGUGUUAUUUAUUUCUGCAUUUCCAAGUUUCUAAGAUCAUUUCAUACUGCCUGAAAAAUUAUUUCUUUUAGCAUAAGAAUGCUACCGUAAAUUUCCUCUAUUUUUAUUCUGAAACAUCUUUAUUUCUGAAGGAUAUUUUAGCUCAGUAUGAAAAGAGGUUAGCAGUUUUUCACAGUGUACAUAUGAGCCCCCCGUCCCCCACUGCAAUAGUUUUUCUUAAAGGGACCUGCCUCUCCCUUAGUUGAGAAUAUUUAAGUGAACUUGAGAAUAUUUAAGUGAACUGGCUUCAACCAUAUGUCAAGUAGUAUGUUUGUGGGCUAUCAAUUUAUUUCUAGGAACCCUAUGAUCAUUUAGCCAUUGCCACCUAUAUGGUUAAAAUUCUCAUUAACAGUGCAUCCCUUGGACUCUUGUGCAGAUUUUACCCAACCCCUCCCAUGCCAAGAUCCUAUGAUCUCUACUGAAAUUGGGAUCUUACUUUCAUUAUAGAAGUUCUGCAUCAUCUACAGUCUAGAGAGGGUGGGUACCACAGAGUUGUCCAAGGAUGGUGGUAAACUCCUCACCAAUGUAUUUCUUAAUACCCUGACGGGAAUGUCUUUUGGCCUUUCUCUGGCUAAGGGAAAAAAUGAACAUAAUAAUUCAUUGAUAGUUACAUCUCCCUCUAAAGCAGAGGUGUCCAAUCUUUUGGCUUCCCUGGGCUACACCAGAAGAAGAAUUUUCUUGAGCCACAAUAACUGAUAGCUAUCAUUAGUGUUCACGUAUUUUAUAUGUGGCCCAAGACAAUUCUUCCAAUGUGGCCCAGGGAUGCCAAAAGAUUGGACACUGGAUUCCAUCCAGUAUGACUUUUCAGAUAUCUAAGAAGAUUUUGCUACACUUAUUACAAUGGUAGUUUUCCCACAGUGUAAUUCUCUGAUAUAGGUUUGAAAUAUUGCAGAAAUUCACUCUACAUUCAUUUAUACAGUUGCUUUUUCUCCUACAAGAGUAUUAAAAUUUAAGUAUUGCAUUGUAAUUGAAGGCAUUCCCAAAUCACUGUGUUUGUAUCACUUUGGUUAAUUGGAGAUUGCUCCAAAGUAAACGUUCUCAAUGUUGGCUGCACUCAACAAAAACUAGAGGGCAAAGAUUUGAUGUAGUCAGGGGUUGGCCAAGUUUUUCUGUAAAGGGCUAGAUAGUAAAUGUUUAACCUUUAUGGCUGUAUAUUAAACUCUUCAGUUAUAGAGGUAAGGAGCCAUAGACUAUGUAAAUGAAUACCUGGCCCAUGGGCUGUAGCUUGAUGACCUCUGAUAUAGUUCAUGAGGUGCAUCCCCACAGAGUAAACAGUAGGAAGGAAAGUGGAUGUGGAGCAGAUAAUGGGAGAAAUUGAGUAUACUCUUAAAUAAAUAAAUAAUGAAUUUUUCAUAUCCUAAUUUUGCUGACAGGGUAACUUGAUUUUUACCCUGAUACAAACCAUUCCUGCCUGAGAAAACCAAAUCAGAUACUAGAUACCCAUAUGUAAUAAGGCAUGCUGCUUGAGGACACCAAAUCAGAUAUUAAAUACCCAUAUGUAAUAAGGCAUGCUGCUUGAGAAAAUCAAAUCAGAUAUUAGAUACCCAUACGUAGUAAGGCAUGCUGCUUGUAUUCGAGUCAGACUGUACACUAUUGUAAGAUAAAUCAGCCUCUCUGAAACAACUCUUAUGGAAACUUGAGAAGCUUCUAAAUGUAUGUACCAAUAUGGCAUGCCAAUGGCAGGUUUGAGGAAAUACACUUCUGAUAAUGUAUUUAGAACUCUAGUACAUGUAAAUAAGGUGUUUUUGGGCUAAAACUUUUAUAAAUUUCACCUCUUACAAAAUUACUUAUAUUUAUCUAAUAACACCUCCUACAAAUGUGCCCUCAAUGCAGCCAUUACAUUAAUGCUCACUAAAUUCAUUCCUAUUCAUAUUCUCUACCUCUCUUUCUACAAAAUAAAAUUGCUUACCUUCCUGAUUAAGGCAAACUAACCCUGAUGGUGUGACCUUUGUCAGCUGGGCAGGUGGUAAUGCCAGAACAGUUUUAAAUACCUGCUUACAAAAGAACGGUUUUCACCGUACAUGGAACAAAACAGGAAGAAUACCUUGGUAAUUUUCUGUGAUGUAUCUUAUAUUUGUUUCACACUGAAUAACAAAUGUCUAUAGUCAGAUUCAAGGAUAACUGUCAGCAUUACCUUAAAUCCAAACUCUGUCUGAAAGUUAAAAUCAUAAAACACCUAAAAACACUUUGUUAUGUUUGUAUGUUUCAACAAGAAAAACUACUGUUUAUUUUUUAUGUCAAUAUUGUAGUUACAUUUUCAGAAUCACAUGCUGUGGGAAAAAAUCAGCAAGCAGAAGGUUUAUAAUAAACCAAAAGAUUUAUUUAUAACAUUUUCUGAAUUCACUUAAAAAACAAAAAGGAAUCCCCCUUCCCUCAAAAUAGAACCGUUUCCUACAGAUUCCAUCCAGUAUGACUUUUCAGAUAUCUAAGGAGAUUUUGCUACACUUAUUACAAUGGUAGUUUUCCCACAGUGUAAUUCUCUGAUAUAGGUUUGAAAUAUUGCAGAAAGUCACUCUACAUUCAUUUAUACAGUUGCUUUUUCUCCUACAAGAGUAUUAAAAUGUAAGUAUUGCAUUGUAAAUGAAGGCAUUCCCAAAUCACUGUGUUUGUAUCACUUUGCUUAAAUAUGAAUUUUCUGAUCUCCAAAGUGCAUCAUCUUUGUAAAGCUCAUCCCUUGUCCAUGCUUUCUGUCCUGGUUGACAGAUGCGGAAUGAGGGCUAAUCUCUGGCUUUCUCCAAUCUAUUGGAUAUGUAUUCUUUCCUGGUAGGAAUUUACACACGUAAAGUAAGGGACUCCUACCAAAUGAAGUCUUCUCAACAUUACCAGAUGGAAGAAUCUUCUCAACAAUAUUGAUUUCACCUUGUUAUUGCAAAAAAAUAAAAGAGUGGUUAUUAAUGGCUUUUCCACAUAUUCCUGGGUUUUUUUUUCUCCAGGGUGGUGAAUAAAGUGUGGGCCAUAUUACUUCACAGUCAUCACUUUCACAUAAGGCUUCUUUCCAAGAGUUCUCUGAAGUAAGGCAUUAUACUUCUUUUUAAAAAAUUCCAUACAUUCAUAGUUUUUCUUUGCAGUGUAAAUUCACUGGUGUUCAGUAAGGAAUGAGUGGUAAUUAAAUGAAUUUUCAUAUUCAUAGGGGUUGUCAAGAGUGUGUGUCCUCUGAUGUUUAGCAAGGUUUGAGCUCCAGCUGAAGGAUUUGUUGCAUACCUUACAUACAUAGGGUUUCUCUCCAGUAUGAGUUCUCUGAUGUAGAAUGAGGGAAAAGCUCCGGCUGAAGGCUUUAUCACAUUCAGCACACGCAUAGGGUUUCUCUCCAGUGUGACUCUUCGUAUGUUGAAUAAGGGAUGCAUGCCAAGUGAAAACUUUACCACAUUCAUCACAUUCAUAGAGCUUUUCUCCAGCAUGAAUUCUCUGAUGUUUAAUAAGGAAUGAGUGACAACGGAAAGCUUUCCUACAUUCAUUACAUUCAUACGGGGUUUUGGUUGUAUGGAUGCUCUGAUGUCGAGUAAGGUGUGAGAAACGGCGAAAUGCCUUCCCACAUUCAAUGCAUUCAUAAGGUUUCUCUCCAGUAUGUGUAAUCUGGUGGCGAAUGAGUUCUGAGCCACUGCUAAAUGCUUUACCACAUUUCCUACAUAUAUAUUGUUUCUUUCCUAUGUGAAUUCUUUGAUGUCGAGUGAGGUUGGAGGCACGGCUAAAGGCCUUUCCACACUCAGUACAUUCAUAAGGUUUCUCCCCAGUGUGCGUUCUCUGGUGUUCAAUAAGAAAUGAAAGGUAACUGAAUGUUUUAUUACAGUCCUUACACUCAUGGGGUUUCUUUCCAGUAUGUAUCAUUUGGUGUUUCACAAGGUUUGAAAUCUGGCUAAAGGUUUUGCCACAUUCCUUACAUGCAUAUGGUUUCUCUCCAGUAUGAGUCCUCUGGUGUAACACCAGGGAAAAGCGUCGACCAAAAGUUUUUCCACAUUCAUGGCAUCCAUAGGGCCUCUCCACAGUACUGAUAUUCAUAUGUUGAGCCAGGGCUUCUUGAUGAGAGACUGUUACUUUCCUAAUACAUCCCUGAUUUUCUUGCAGCAUCUCAGUAUGAUCCUUGCAUUUCCAGCCUCCUUUAAAACUGGAAUACACAGGGCCUUGACUUAGAAUUCUUUCCAUGAUCAAAUACUGGGAUGAGUCAUCAUAAAUGACAUUUUUUGGUGAAAAGUCUUUGAUCUCACCACUUGACUCUGAAACUGAAAGAUACCAAAAAAAAAGUGAAUGUUUCUUUUUCCUGUAUUGAAUAAAAUAAGGCCAUUUCUCCCUUCUUUAGCAACAGAAUGAAGUUUCAAAAAAUCUUAUCAAUAGCAGCUUUCACAGCUGUGACUGAAAUCUGAGUAGUAUGCCCAGAACUUCAGAAAAGAUCAAACAGAGAUAGACAUAUAGGUAAAUAAAGAGAAAGUGUAAACGUAAGUAAUUGAAAGAGCAGGGAAAAUAGAGCUAUCAGGAAAUAUUUGUGAAGGAUAGGUUGCUAGUCUUCUUCACCACCAUUUAAACGGUAUUUACUGCCAGAAUUAUCUAAAAAUGGCAAUUUCAUAAUGCUGCUACUAAACACUAAGUGUUCGUCAGAUUGCACAAAGACAUUAGAUUCUGUUCACUUAGUGCCUCUGGAACAUCUUAUAAUAAUCUAAAUGAAAAAAAAAGCGGUUUCUCUGAAAACUUGCCUAUGAUCCUCCAACUCUACCUUCUGAACUAGUAUGAAGCUCAUAUUUGGUAUAAUUAUGUCUUUUCUGGGACCUAUUUGAGGGUGGAAUGUGGGAGGAGGGUAAGGAUUAAAAACCUGACUAUUGGGCAUUAUGCUGAUUACCUGGGUGACAAAAUUAUCUGCACACCAAACCCCCAUGACACACAAUUUGCUCAUGUAACAUGAGUAACCUUUAACCUAAAAUGAAAGUUGGACAGAAAAAUAAAGUGUCUUAAUAUCAAA